CAGGCAUGAGCCACCGUGCCUGGCCAGUUCUUGUAUUAAUGCCCAUUUGUUUUUGUCUGGCCAGAGAACAGAAAGCCUCUCAGUGAAGACAUAGCAACCCCCUGGUUUUUCUGCCCUGCUGGUAGAUGGUGUUCCUGUGGGAAAUAGAAGAGCUAGGGCCCGGAGGGUGGGUGGGGAGGCCAGGGAAGAACUAUGCCCCUCUCCUGGCCCAGACUCUGACCUUCCAGUUGGGCAAGGGAUCCGUAGAGUUCUGCCUUCGAGGUUCCCUCAGCUCUCAGGCCUCAGGAGGAAAUAGGUCCUGAGUAGGUCCAGCCUGGGCCCUUCCUGUGUAUGGGGAAACAGAAACCAAGACAAGCCCUUUCUUUUCAGCCACCAGCCCUGGGUGUCUGAUGGGCCUCUAGGGAGGCACCUCCAGCAGCUUCCAUCCCAUUCUAUGUGGCGGUGAAGGAGUCUGGCAGACACCACUGGGAUCUCAGGCAGCGCUGUUGAUAGUCCAGAAAUAGGUGCCUUCACCCUUCAUUCCUGCUGUGCCCUCCUCUCUAAGGAGCCAGUGGCUGGGAGCAGUGCUGGAGGAUCAAGGAAGCAGAGAUGGACGGUGAGGCAGUCCGCUUCUGCACAGAUAACCAGUGUGUCUCCCUGCACCCCCAAGAGGUGGACUCUGUGGCAAUGGCUCCUGCAGCCCCCAAGAUACCGAGGCUCGUUCAGGCUACCCCGGCAUUUAUGGCUGUGACCUUGGUCUUCUCUCUUGUGACUCUCUUUGUAGUGGGUAAGCCCCCAGGUGACCCAAAUCUCACUAACUUUCUCUCCUUUCAGCACAAAGUCCCCAGGGGCCCCAGAUGCACACUCUCUGGGCCUCUCUGCUCCCAGAAAGAUCAUUCCACCUCCAGCUCCAGGCCCAAGCCACAGCUUCCCUGGGAACAGAUAAAGGCCACUGUCCAAGGGGGAGCCUCCCAAGAACUGAGGUUCAUGAGGGAAACCCUGGGAGGGUCUUUGCUGCUAUCUCCCCGGUUCUGGAACUCUACCUCUGUGUGGGACAGCGUAUCCUCCCAGGCUCAGGGCUGGGGAUUUGCUGACCUGGAAAAAUGGAAUGUCUCAGUUCAACAGCAGACAAGACCUGUUCCGAAGCCUGUGCAAGCCGUAAUUCUGGGAGACAACAUUACUGGGCAUUUACCUUUUGAACCCAACAAUCAUCACCACUUUGGCAGGGAGGCAGAAAUGCGAGAGCUUAUCCAGACAUUUAAAGGCCACAUGGAGAAUUCCAGUGCCUGGGUAGUAGAAAUCCAGAUGUUGAAGUGCAGAGUGGACAAUGUCAAUUCGCAGCUCCAGGUGCUCGGUGAUCAUCUGGGAAACACCAAUGCUGACAUCCAGAUGGUAAAAGGAGUUCUAAAGGAUGCCACUACAUUGAGUUUGCAGACACAGAUGUUAAGGAGUUCCCUGGAGGGAACCAAUGCUGAGAUCCAGAGGCUCAAGGAAGACCUUGAAAAGGCAGAUGCUUUAACUUUCCAGACGCUGAAUUUCUUAAAAAGCAGUUUAGAAAACACCAGCAUUGAGCUCCACGUGCUAAGCAGAGGCUUAGAAAAUGCAAACUCUGAAAUUCAGAUGUUGAAUGCCAGUUUGGAAACGGCAAAUACCCAGGCUCAGUUAGCCAAUAGCAGUUUAAAGAACGCUAAUGCUGAGAUCUAUGUUUUGAGAGGCCAUCUAGAUAGUGUCAAUGACUUGAGGACCCAGAACCAGGUUUUAAGAAAUAGUUUGGAAGGAGCCAAUGCUGAGAUCCAGGGACUAAAGGAAAAUUUGCAGAACACAAAUGCUUUAAACUCCCAGACCCAGGCCUUUAUAAAAAGCAGUUUUGACAACACUAGUGCUGAGAUCCAGUUCUUAAGAGGUCAUUUGGAAAGAGCUGGUGAUGAAAUUCACGUGUUAAAAAGGGAUUUGAAAAUGGUCACAGCCCAGACCCAAAAAGCAAAUGGCCGUCUGGACCAGACAGAUACUCAGAUUCAGGUAUUCAAGUCAGAGAUGGAAAAUGUGAAUACCUUAAAUGCCCAGAUUCAGGUCUUAAAUGGUCAUAUGAAAAAUGCCAGCAGAGAGAUACAGACCCUAAAACAAGGAAUGAAGAAUGCUUCAGCCUUAACUUCCCAGACCCAGAUGUUAGACAGCAAUCUGCAGAAGGCCAGUGCCGAGAUCCAGAGGUUAAGAGGGGAUCUAGAGAACACCAAAGCUCUAACCAUGGAAAUCCAGCAGGAGCAGAGUCGCCUGAAGACCCUCCAUGUGGUCAUUACUUCACAGGAACAGCUACAAAGAACCCAAAGUCAGCUUCUCCAGAUGGUCCUGCAAGGCUGGAAGUUCAAUGGUGGAAGCUUAUAUUAUUUUUCUAGUGUCAAGAAGUCUUGGCAUGAGGCUGAGCAGUUCUGCGUGUCCCAGGGAGCCCAUCUGGCAUCUGUGGCCUCCAAGGAGGAGCAGGCAUUUCUGGUAGAGUUCACAAGUAAAGUGUACUACUGGAUCGGUCUCACUGACAGGGGCACAGAGGGCUCCUGGCGCUGGACAGAUGGGACACCAUUCAACGCCGCCCAGAACAAAGCGCCUGGUUCCAAGGGAUCCUGCCCACUCAGAAAGUAUAUUAUUGUGAAUUCUGGGAUGGGAGCUUGCAGCUUCAUAGACACCCCUCCCUGUCCCUGGAUCCUCAGUAACUAAGAGCAACCUGAGCACAGACACCCUCAGGGUACUCCUUCUCCCAGCCCUGUCCUCAUCCUAGGGCCACUAGGGGAUGAAGGACCCAUCUCAAGUCAGCUCCCUAGACUCAUCCCAUGUCAGCUCCCUAGGAGCCACAGCACCAGGAAGGGAUGCUGCCUUCAUCUAACAGUAUAAAGCCCUGUUGUCUUCGGGUUUUGGGAAAAGAAUCAGUCUGACAACUGGCGGCACAAGAAUGGGCAGACUGAAGACUGUGUCCAAAUUCAGCAGAAGUGGAAUGACAUGACCUGUGACACCCCCUAUCAGUGGGUGUGCAAGAAGCCCAUGGGCCAGGGUGUGGCCUGAGGGCAGGCCAGAGCUGAGGGGCUGCUCCUGCUUGCCAAUACUGACCCUCCUCCUCGAUGCCUUCGGAGCCUCUGAGCUCUGCUUGUUCUCUGGGACCUUCCGUUGGCCUUGUGGACUUCCUGCCUUGUUCUUUGAUUCAGCCCUUUCAAACAUGCUUACCUCGAGUGACCCAGUGACAUCAGUGGCUUCUCAAGGGAAGAGCCUUGCUGUGCCCCUGUAGCCUCAGCACCCAGCACAGGCCUGUCAGACAGCAGGUCCUCAAUAAAUACUCGCUGGAUCAACAAAA